AGAAGCAGGUUGGCUGUGAUGACAGCACAGAGCUCAGGAACGCUGCCUGAGGACCCUGGGGCCUACGAGGAGGAGAAGAGGGCAGGAGCUGGUGGGGUGCUUGCAGAGACCCUGGGCUCCUAUCCUGCCAUAAGCCUCGCUGUCUCCUGAUAUCUGCAGCCAGGCCCUACUGACACCCCCAGGCCUGAGUGCAAGCAGAGACCCCACCAUUCCCAGGCCCUGGAGGACUGGUCCACCUUAACUGGGCAGCCCUUGGGGCAGGCGCUGGCCGGUGCCUCAGCCCAGGCCUCUGUGCUCUGCAUGCACUGCCAGCCUGCCAUCAGGCCUCUAUUGCAGCCCUGAACCAUGAUCCAGGGCACCUUGGAGCCAGAUGGUCCCCUCUGGGGCUGGGACUGGGACAGUGACAAUGACUGGGAUAGUGCUGUGCUGGCCCUCCUGGCGCUGGCUGUGGUGGCUGCCACAGCGCUGGCCUUACACUGGUUUGGCUCCGGGCACGAUCAAGAGGCGGCAGAACCGGUGUCCACAGCCCUCGGGGCUCAACCUCAUCAGGCAGGAGGAGCUGAGCUGGCCCUGCAACCGAAGUCUAAGGUCAGUGAUGGCAGCGAGGGGCAGAGCCCAGGGCAGGGGAAACCAGAGCCCCCAGGACGCGGCCAGCAGAGCCCUGUCCCUGCUGCAGCGCCGGGCGGGGGCCUGGCCGCCAUGGCCCGGCUUCCACUCAAGACGGCUGUCGAGGAGGCCCGCAGAGAGGCAUUAGGACAGCAACGGGGCAGUGCCACCCCCGCGGCCCCCCGAGCGGAAGGAAAGGAGCCUCCCAGGCCAGGCACUGCCCUCCUGGGCAGGAGCGAAGCAGGGGGGAUGUCCGCCCCCCUCCUGAUCCACUUCACUCCUCGGAGCCCUGGCAGCGAAGCGGAGGCGGAGACAGGUGGUGUCAGGGCGUCCUCUCGCCAGGCCGCAGGCCCCGCGGGGCAACAGGACACUGGCCCCUGGCAGGCGGGCGCGGGGCCCUCGGGCUCGAUGGGGAGAGGCCGGGGCCGGCGGCGGCGGAUGGACGCUGGCUCGGGAGACAGAGCCCGCCGCCCCCGGAAACUGGACCCGCUCCGCCUGGGCGCCGCGGGGAGCGUGUGGGACGCGGUGGACGGGGCCGCCGCCCUGGACGCCCACGCGCGCGGCCUCCCCACAGGACCCCCACUCGCCCAGGAGCCCGCACUCCCGGCGCUGCCCGCUCCCCGCGCCCUGCAGCCUGGGUCUCAGACGGAAGGCUCUGGGGCCAAGGGUGGCUGGAGCAGGGAGGCCUCGGGGGUCCCUGCCCCCGGAGGAGGCUGGCCCUGGGUCAGCAGGGAGGUCCCGGGCACCCGGAGCUUUGGCCCAGCCCCAGACUCCACGCGCCCCUGGCUAGAGAGUCCGCCUCAAGGUCGCCCACUCUCGUCCCAAGGGCCGGGUGCCACAGGGGCCUACGAUGCCGGCGAGGCCGGGGCUGACAGCUCCCGAGAUAACAGUCCUGCCGCUGACCUGGGGCCCACCCGGCCCCCGGAGCAAGCAAAGCCGGCUGCAGCCGGCCACAGCCGCGCGCCCUCCCGGAGCCGUGAGCCUCGCCCGCGCUCCGCCUCCCCGCCCGCAGCUCCCGGCCCGGGGUUCCCACCUGAAGCCCUGACUCUCCCCUCUCCUUCAGACUUUUUGCCCCUGGAGGUUACCCAGGAUCCUUCCGUGGGCGAAAAUCUCAGAGCGGCGCCAGCCCCAAGUUCAGCCUCAGCCCAAGUCUUAACUUCAGCUCCAGCCUCAGUCCUAGCCCCAGCCCUGGCUUCAUCCCCCAGCUCAGCACCAACCUCAGCCACCACCUCAACCUCAUCCCCCACCUCAGCCCCAGCCCCAGCUCCAACCUCAGCUCCAACUUCAACCCCAGCCCCAGCCCCAAGUCCAGCUGCAGCCGCAACUCCAGCCCCAGCCCCAGUCCCAGUCCCAACCCUCACACCCCCAUCCCCAGCCCUAACCCCAGUCCCAACCCCAGCCCUAAGCCCAGCUCCAACUCCAGCCCUAACCCCAGCCGCAUCCCCAGCCCUAACCCCAGUCCCAACCCCAGCCCUAAGCCCAGCUCCAACUCCAGCCCCAACCCCAGCCGCAUCCCCUGCCCCAGCCCCCACCUCAGCCCCAACCCCAACCCCAGCCGCAUCCCCUGCCCCAGCUGACGGGUCAAAGCCUCAGGAGAGUGUGGCUCUCCCCAGGCGCUACCAGGAGGGGCAGGUCUCAGCCAGCUGGGGAAACCUUAUUGCCAUGGUUCUUAGAAGCCACCCCUUCCCCAGGCAAGACAGGCCCCAAGGGAGUGUCCCGAGGGCGGUUCCCGGGAGCCCCGUGGGUCCCAGCACUUCCACACACUCUGAGGACAGACACGGCCCCUCUUCUUCAGUGGGGACAGUCAUAGGGACAGGUACAGGGGGCCUGGUUGAGGCUGGAGGUCAGCCACAGCCAAGAAGCUCCGAGACCAACGGAUCGCCCAGCCCAGACCCUCCCCCAGGCCUAAGAGGAGAGGGAACCAGGGAGAAAAGUCUAGACCCGCUGCCCCAAGCCGCGAUGCCCAGGGGCCCCGCACAGCCCCCCGCGCAGAGGCCGCCUGGCCCCGCGGCCUCCUCCUCUGCGAGGCGCUCACAGCCGGUACCCCAGCUACGGAAACGCAGCAGGUGCGAAAUCGCCCCGAGCUCGGAGCAGGAGGUCAGGCCGGCCGCCUCGGGGGACCCUCAAGGGGAGGCGCCGGGGGAGGGGGGCAGCCCUGCCGGCCGCAGCGGGGCGCUCACGGAAAAGCAGGAGGAGGCCCGGAAGCUCAUGGUGUUUCUGCAGAGGCCCGGGGGUUGGGGGGUGGUGGAGGGGCCCCGGAAGCCCAGCUCCCGGGCCCUGGAGCCCGCCACGGCGGCAGCCCUGCGGCGGCGGCUGGACCUGGGCAGUUGCCUGGACGUGCUGGCCUUUGCCCAGCAGCACGGAGAGCCCGGCCUGGCGCAGGAGACCUACGCGCUGAUGAGCGACAACCUGCUGCGAGUGCUGGGAGACCCGUGCCUCUACCGCCGGCUGAGCGCGGCCGACCGCGAGCGCAUCCUCAGCCUGCGGACCGGCCGGGGCCGGGCGGUGCUGGGCGUCCUCGUACUGCCCAGCCUCUACCAGGGGGGCCGCUCAGGGCUCCCCAGGGGCCCUCGUGGCGAGGAGCCUCCUGCGGCGGCCCCUGUGUCCCUGCCUCUACCUGCGCACCUGCAUGUGUUCAACCCCCGGGAGAACACCUGGCGGCCCCUGACCCAGGUGCCCGAGGAGGCCCCGCUUCGGGGCUGCGGUCUCUGCACCAUGCACAACUACCUGUUUCUGGCGGGGGGCAUCCGUGGCUCCGGUGCCAAGGCCGUCUGCUCCAACGAGGUCUUCUGCUACAACCCUCUGACCAACAUCUGGAGCCAGGUUCGGCCCAUGCAGCAGGCCCGAGCCCAGCUCAAGCUGGUGGCCCUGGACGGGCUGCUCUAUGCCAUCGGUGGCGAAUGCCUGUACAGCAUGGAGUGCUACGACCCGCGAACAGACGCCUGGACCCCACGCGCGCCACUCCCCGCAGGCACCUUCCCUGUGGCCCACGAGGCUGUGGCCUGCCGUGGGGACAUCUACGUCACCGGGGGUCACCUCUUCUACCGCCUGCUCAGGUACAGCCCCGUGAAGGAUGCUUGGGACGAGUGCCCAUACAGUGCCAGCCACCGGCGUUCCAGCGACAUCGUGGCACUGGGGGGCUUCCUGUACCGCUUCGACCUGCUGCGGGGCGUGGGCGCCGCCGUGAUGCGCUACAACACAGUGACCGGCUCCUGGAGCAGGGCUGCCUCCCUGCCCCUGCCCGCCCCCGCCCCACUGCACUGCACCACCCUGGGCAACACCAUUUACUGCCUCAACCCCCAGGUCACUGCCACCUUCACGGUCUCUGGGGGGACUGCCCAGUUCCAGGCCAAGGAGCUGCAGCCCUUCCCCUUGGGGAGCACCGGGGUCCUCAGUCCAUUCAUCCUGACUCUGCCCCCUGAGGACCGGCUGCAGACCUCACUCUGAGUGGCAGGCAGAGAACCAAAGCUGCUUCGCUGCUCUCCAGGGAGACCCUCCUGGGAUGGGCCUGAGAGGCCGGGGCUCAGGGAAGGGGCUGGGAUCGGAACUUCCUGCUCUUGUUUCUGGACAACUUUCCCCUUCUGCUUUAAAGGUUGUCGAUUAUUUUGAAGCCCAGACUCCCUCAGCCUCUUUCUGCCCCUCACUCCACACCCAGACUGUUUCCUGACUCAAUUCCGUACCUACUUACAGACCCUCUCAGCUUGCUGACACCCCCCUGUCUGUGGGACUCCCUAUUCCCUAGAGCCAGGGACUGAUGCGUCUCCACAGACAAGGACUUGGCUCGCUGGAGCUCUGCUGAGCCGAGAGAGGAGGGGGUAGAAAACAUUCACACUUCCUAUGCUCUGUCAGCAGGACAGGGAGCAAAAACGUCCCCAGGCAACGCCCUCGCCUCUGGGACUUUCUGCCUGUCCUAAGGCCUCCCCAGGUACCAACCCCGUAGCUAUCUGGGUCUGUUUGGCACUGUGGAUUCUCAAGGGCCUAGAACCCUUGCCUCUGAAACUGGUCCGCUGGUGCAGCCCUGCUGUCUGCAGCUCCUGCCCAUACCCCCAGCCCACACCAGGCCAGGCCCACUCCGGGCUCACCACCCUCUGCAGCCUUGUGGGGCUCUCCCAGCCCCUCCAGAAGCCCACCCCACUUCUCGCCAACCCCCGAUCUCUAAAUGAGGCCUGAGCGUCACCCUAGUUCUGCCCCUUUUUAGCUGUGUAGACUUGGACGAGACAUUUGACUUCCCUUUCUCCUUGUCUAUAAAAUGUGGACAGUGGACGUCUGUCACCCAAGAGAGUUGUGGGAGACAAGAUCACAGCUAUGAGCACCUCGCACGGUGUCCAGGAUGCACAGCACAAUCCAUGAUGCGUUUUCUCCCCUUACGCACUUUGAAACCCAUGCUAGAAAAGUGAAUACAUCUGACUGUGCUCCACUCCAACCUCCAGCCUGGAUGUCCCUGUCUGGGCCCUUUUUCUGUUUUUUAUUCUAUGUUCAGCACCACUGGCACCAAAUACAUUUUAAUUCACCGAAAGCA